GAGAUUCCUCGGCGGGUAGGCAGCGGUGCUGGGCAUGCUCAGUGGGCAGGACCCGUUAGAGUGGCGAGUAAGGAAGCGUUGGCUCUUCUCCGGGUCUGCCUUCCCCGGUUCAGGCCCCGGCCCUGGGCUUUUGUGUGCGCGUAGCUGCAGCCGCCACUGCCUCCUCGCGGGGCUGCCCGACCCCAGAUGCCGUCAGGCCUGUCCGGUUUCCGCCGUUAACCUCGCCGCGCGGCCGGGAGGAGGAGCGGGGCGGGGCCGGCGGCGGGCGGCCGGGCUGGAGGGCCCUGCCGGGGGUGGGGGUGGGUGCGGGGAGCCCCGCGGGGGGUGGGGGGCGGGGGCGGGCGCGGAGUCACGGGGGUGGGGUCACUCGCGGUGGCUCGGGGAGGCCAGCUGGGAGGGGAGGGGGCCGUGGGGGCGGCUCGGCGGAACCAGCCCCGGCUGGGCAGCAGCGGGGACGCCGGGGGCCGGGGCCAGGGCUUUCCGGGCUUCGGUGAGGCCGCCGUGGGCCCCAUCUUCCGGCGGUCGCCGGAGUUUGUGGUGAUUGUUGCUGCCGCCGCCACCGCCCCGGCUGCCAUCUCCUCCUCCUGGGCCGCCGCCUCCUCCUCUUCCUCCUCCUCCUGGGCCGGGCUGAUCCCCUCCCCGCUGCCGCCUCCUCCUGGGCUGGGCCCGCGGUGUCUCGUCCCCUCGCGGAGCCGCUCCUGCCGCCGCCGCCGCCGCCUCCUCAUUCAUCCUCGUGCACCAUAGGCGGCACAGGCACCAAGAUGUCCAACCGAGUGGUCUGCCGAGAAGCCAGUCACGCCGGGAGCUGGUACACAGCCUCAGAUGGAGUCUCACUGUGUCACCCAGGCUGGAGUACAGUGUCGUUAUCUCAGCUCACUGCAACCUCCGCUUCCCAGGUUCAAGCGAUUCUCGUGCCUCAGCCUCCCAAAUCUGGGAUUACAGGACCGCAGCUGAAUGCACAGCUAGAAGGUUGGCUUUCACAAGUACAGUCUACAAAAAGACCUGCUAGAGCCAUUAUUGCCCCCCAUGCAGGAUAUACGUACUGUGGGUCUUGUGCUGCCCAUGCUUAUAAACAAGUGGAUCCGUCUAUUACCCGGAGAAUUUUCAUCCUUGGGCCUUCUCAUCAUGUGCCCCUCUCUCGAUGUGCACUUUCCAGUGUGGAUAUAUAUAGGACACCUCUGUAUGACCUUCGUAUUGACCAAAAGAUUUACGGAGAACUGUGGAAGACAGGAAUGUUUGAACGCAUGUCUCUGCAGACAGAUGAAGAUGAACACAGUAUUGAAAUGCAUUUGCCUUAUACAGCUAAAGCCAUGGAAAGCCAUAAGGAUGAGUUUACCAUUAUUCCUGUACUGGUUGGAGCUCUGAGUGAGUCAAAAGAACAGGAAUUCGGAAAACUCUUCAGUAAAUAUCUAGCGGAUCCUAGUAAUCUCUUUGUGGUUUCUUCUGAUUUCUGCCAUUGGGGUCAAAGGUUCCGUUACAGUUACUAUGAUGAAUCCCAGGGGGAGAUUUAUAGAUCCAUUGAACAUCUAGAUAAAAUGGGUAUGAGUAUUAUAGAACAAUUAGACCCUGUAUCUUUUAGCAAUUACUUGAAGAAAUACCAUAAUACUAUAUGUGGAAGACAUCCCAUUGGGGUGUUAUUAAAUGCUAUCACAGAGCUCCAGAAGAAUGGAAUGAAUAUGAGUUUUUCGUUUUUGAAUUAUGCCCAGUCGAGCCAGUGUAGAAACUGGCAAGACAGUUCAGUGAGUUAUGCAGCUGGAGCACUCACGGUCCACUGAAGCUCUGAAUCCUCAGGGAUGCCACCUGCACAUUCUCAUACUCUGUCCGGGGUCCCAGCCUAGCCUUUACCACGAUACUGGUCCUGGUUUGGGGGGAUUCUGAAACCUCAAACUAAUAGAACUUUCUUCUCUUUUUUUCUAGUAGGUGUAGUCCUUCCUUAAUUUCAACUCAUUAAAAAAUGCUUUAUAGUUUAGGGCAGUGGAAGGAAGGCUGGCAUCAAAAUAUUUUGAUCAAAAAAGAUGACAAUGUAAAGGCUCAGUUGUGGCAGACAGUUUUUUGAAAGUAACUUGUAAAGCAUUUACCAUAUCCUAAAUUUGCACUCUUUGCAGACUUGUGCACAUAUAUUCCGCUUUCAGAAUAGUUUUGCAAAUUGUACACAAACAAACAAAAAGGUGGAAGCUUUUUAAUAAAGAAAUUGCAUUUAUAAAUGAUCUGUAUUAGAAUAUAAUAAAUCUCCAGUUAUAGUCAAUUACUACCCAUGUUGUACAACAGAUACCUUCUAUUUUAGUUGCUAAUAAAGGGCUACACAACUCAAAA